CACUUCAGCCCGGGCAACAGAGUGAGACUCCGUCUCUAAAUAAAUAAGUAAUAGCUGACACAUGUAAGUUGCUACCCUGGCCCUUCAUUUUACAGAUGAGGAAAAUGAAGUUCAGAGAGCUUAAGAAACUUGCCAGAGUCAUACAGCUAACUCAGGCACUCUGGCCUUGGAAUUUAUGUUCUUAUCCACCACAGCAGGAGGCCUAUCAGAGAAGGGGUGGUAUUUGUCCAAAGCCCCCUACUUCACUAUGUGUCAAAGAAAUAAAUAACACUCUCCUAUGGAACAGGGACAAGUCUCAUUUCUGGCUGGGUUUGGCUCCUGUGCCAAGUGCUUUCCUCCUGCACGGGGGUGGAGAGAGCAGCCCUGUGAGACGCAGCUCAGCAUCUCUGUUCCUCGCCAUCAGGGUCCCUGCAUCUGCCUUGUCUCCUGCCCCCACUCAAGGGCCUGCCCAGGUCAUGGGGUGUAUAGAAGAGGCACAGGCAUGAAGAACUGGUGAUCCCCCUGUGAAACCCCACGUUUCCCCCCAAGUACUAAGACAUUUAAUAAUGGGUCCUGCCCUAUACGUUUAGGGUUGAGGGGAUACUUUCUAAAGAGGUAUCAGCUACUAUCACCUGUGCAAACAGUGCUAGGGAUGCUGAUUCCCUUUUCCAGAAACAUCAGCCACUCAAUCUCUUUCUUGGUGAGAGCUGAUAGAUUGUUGGUAGGUUGAAAUUGGUCACAGUGGGAAUAUUGACACCACAGAGAUAGGCAGAUGCUACAAAUUAGGGAUGCCCCCUACACCAACCCAGAAAAUUGAUUGUUAAAUAUUGUAGUGUCUUUUUUUCUGACACCAAAUGUGUAUCCUAUAAGUCAAUUCAAUUCCGACAUUAUCCAGUUAGUGCGGACCCCACAGUUUAAGGGGUCUGUUCCACAAGACGGCACUCACAUCAGAUACUAAUCCCAAGUCCUCCUCCUCUCUGCAGUUUGAAGAGACCCACCUAUCUCUUUGCCUUUAUCAGGCAUCGCCAGCUCCGAGUUAAUCACUGGGGCUUCCAGGUACUGCUGUUUAUGGAGGAUCCCUCCCACUGAAGCCUGGGUGGUUAAAGAGAUGUCAAUGGAUCCUGGAGAUGCUUUUUGGCCUUUCAGUUUCCUAACUCUGUGCUGCAGGAGACAUUCAAGGGAAAUCUGGAUGACUUAGCGGCUGCUUUCAGGUUUGCCACUGGUGUGGUGUGGAAGGAGAUACCAGCUGUUCUCUAGAUUAAGGGGAAAAUUAGCUUAGAACCCUUAGGAGGGAUUUAGGUUUGAUCUACGAACUUUCUGAUUGUAGCAGUUACUAAGCUGCUAGAAUUACCUUGGAUAUCUGGGAAAUCUUCCUGGAUAUAUUUAAGGACUGGAUAAUUCCCAUCUGUUUAUAACGGCUUUUAUGGAAUCAUUCUGGAGGGAGGAGAGUGGCCUGGAAACUCUCACAGAGUCAGGCAGAUAAAAAGUAUUUUCUCUUUUCUCCUUGUGGUGGUCUUUUCCCUUUGCCUUUAGAAUAUACUCCACCAUUUCCUCCUUUAUGGAUGUGCUUACUGUCUGUUGGUCUAAUGGCAAAUCUCUGAGACAAAAAGCUAUGUCUAGCCCUGAGAUUAAGGCAUCCUUGGGCUUCAUCCAAAUGGGAGACAGCCGAGCUCAUGCAGGGCUUCCACUUUAUUUGGAAAUGAAAGUAGAAGCACUUCUGCUGUUUUGUUUUCCACUGGUCUUGAGAAAGCCACAGACGCUCAGCAAAGACUGCAGGUCUAGCCAGGGGACACAGGGUUAAGAGAGAAGAGGCUGAAGUCGUGUUAGAUCAGUGGUCUUCACAAGGGGCUCUGCCUGCUUCUUUAUUUGUAGGGUUUAUUUAGCUCCCUCCACAAACAGACUGAAAGUUUUCACAGGGAAAUUGCUUAAUUUUCAGCCAUUUCCUGCUUGCCAGAGUUGAAUGUAAAAGACAGAAUCAGGCUCCUGGGAUAAGUACAAUGGACUGGACUAGAUUUGCAAGGCCUGGGAGACAGAAGAAGGUUCUGACCCAGACCCAUUCUUCUUUUCUAUUUUUUAAUAGAUGUGUUCAGCUAUUGACAUAUAAUAGACUGCAUUAUAUGUAAAGUGUACCAUUUGAUCAGUUUUAAUAUACAUUUGUAUAUGUGUAUAUGUGUGUGUGUAUGAAUAAAUAAGUCCAGGAAACUAUCAUGGAAUCAUAUAUCAUAUUCAUGAACUUAAGGUAGCAGACAUAUCCACACCCCCCAAAAUUUCCUGUUGCCCCUUGGUAAUCCCUCCUUCUCACUCCUGCCUACUGUCACUUCUUUUCUUCUAACAAAUGUUUUCAUUUUUUAGAGUUUUAUAUAAAUGAAAUGUGCCUUUCUUGUCUGGCUUCUGUCACUCACAUGAUUAUUUUGAGAUUUGUUCAUUUUGGUGCUUUGGAUCAACAGUUCAUUCCCUUUAAUUAAGAAUGGCAUUCCAUAAUUUGUCUAUCCAUUUACCUGUCAACGAACAUUUGGGUCAUUGUUUUUUGCUAUUACAAAUAAAAGUGCUAUGAACAGUCAUGUACAAGUCUUUGUAUGUACACAUGCUUUUCUUCUCUUGAGUAAAUAUUUAGGACUAGGAUGGCUGGAUUAAACACUUGUUUGACUUUCUAAGAAACUGUCAAAUGUUUUCCAAAGGAAUGGUACUGCUUUACAUUUUUACUAGCAAUAUAUGAGAGUUCCAGGUGCUCCACAUCUUUGCCAAGAGUUGGUACAGUCAAUCUUCAUAAUGUUAGCCAUUCCAAUAGGUGUGUAGUGGUAUUUCAUUGUGGUUUUCAGUUGCAUGUCUCUUAUAAGUAAUGAGGGUGAAUAUCUUUUUAUGUAGUUGUUUGAUAUCCCUAUAUCUUGUUUGGUGAAGUGCCUGUUCAAAUGUUUUGCCCAUUUUAAAAAGUGGGUUGUUUGUUUUCUUAUUAAUGAGUUUUGAAAGUUCUUUAUGUGUUCUAGAUAAAAACCCUGUAUUAGAUAUGUGUUUUGUAAAUACUUUUUCUCAGUCUGUGGCUUGCUUUUCAUUCACUUAAAUUGUAUCUUUCAAAGAGCAGAUGUUUCAAAUUUUGAUGAAGACCAAUUUGUCGUAUUUUUUUCAAAUGAAUUGCACUUUUGUUGUUAUACCCAAGAAACUUUUGCCAAAGCUAAGGUCACAAAGAUGUUUCCUUCUUGAAGUUUUAUGUUUACAGGUUUUACAUUUAGGUCCAUGAUACAUUGUAGUUAUUUUUUGUAUAUGGUACAAAGUGCGAAUUAAAAUUCUUUUUGCAGCUGGGUGCGGUGGCUCAUGCCUGUAAUCCCAGCACUUUGGGAGGCCAAGGUGGGCGGAUCAUGAAGUCAGGAGAUCAAGACCAUCCUGGCUAUGGUGAAACCCCAUCUCUACUAAAAAUAUAAAAAAUUAGCUGGGCGUGGUGGCGGGCGCCUGUAGUCCCAGGUACUCGGGAGGCUGAGGCAGGAGAAUGGCGUAACCUGGGAGGUGGAGCUUGCAGUAAGCCAGAGAUCGCGCCACUGCACUCCAGCCUGAGCAAGACUCUGUCUCAAAACAAAAAACAAAAAAGCUGUUUUUGCAAAUGGAUAUUCAAUUGUUUCAGUAUCAUUUGUUGGAAAAAUCUAUGCUUUAUCCUCUGAAUUGCCUUGCAUCUUUGCCAAAAAAUCAUUUAUAUACAUGGGUCUAUUUUUGGCUUCUCUGUUCUAUAUUCUGUUCCAUUUAUCUGUUUGUGUGUCUUUAUGCCAGUAGCACUGUCUUGCCUACUAUAGCUUUAUAAUAAGUCUUGAAAUCAGGUAGUGUUUGUCUUCCAAUUUUGUUCUUCUUUUUCAAAGUUGUUUUGGCUAUUCUAGGUUUUUCUCAUUUUUGUGUGAAUUCUAAAUCAGGUUAUCAGUUUCUACAAAUAAGCCUGGUGGGAUUUUGACUGGAAUUGAGAUGAAUCUAUUGGACUUAGGAAGAAAUGACAUCUUAAUAAUAUUGAGUCUCUCGAUCCCAUGAACAUGGCAUAUCUCUCCAUUUGUUUUAGGUCUUCUUUGUAUUCUCAUUGAUAUUUUAUAGCUUUCAGUGUAUAAGUAUUAGACAUCCUUUGUCAGAUAUAUUCAUAUCUCAUAUUUUUAUACAAUUGCAAAUGAUAUUUUUAUUUCAAUUUUAAUUUUUUUUUGUUAGUAUAGAUAAAUACAAUUGAUUAUCAUAUACUGAGUGUGUGUCCUGCAACCUUGUCAAAUUCACUUAUUUUAUAAGUAGCUUUUUGUGAAUUUCAUCAGAUUUUUUUUAUAUAAGCACUCCUGCUGUCUGGGAAUAAAGACAAUUUAACUUUUUCCUUUCCAAUCUGAAUGUAUUUUAUUUCUUUUUCUUGCUCCAUUGAGCUAGCUAAAAUCUCCAACACAAUGUUGAAUAGAAGUGGUAAGAACAGAUAUUCUUGUCUUUUUCUUGACCCCAGGAGCAAAACAUUUGGUCUUUCACCCUUAAGUAUGAUGUUAGCUGUUGUUUUCGUAGAUGCCCAUUUUCGUGUUGGGCCAGUUCCUUCCUAUUCCUAGUUCUCUUAGUUUUUAUCAGGAGUAGCUUUUGUCAGAUGCGUUUUCUGUAUCUAUUGAGAUGAUCAAAAGGUUUAUCUUUUAAAAUUUGUUAAUAUGGUAAAUUACAUUAUUGAUUUUCAAAUGUUAAACCAUUCUUGCAUUUCUCAGAUAAACCCUGGUUGGUCAGGAUUAUCAUCUUUUUAUAUGGUGUUGAACUCAAUCUGUUACAAUUUCCUGAAGAAUGAUUACAUCUGUGUUCAUAAGGGAUAUUGGCCUAUUUUUUUUCUGUAAUAUCUUCAUUCAGUUUUGGUAUCAGGGUAAUGCUAGCCUCAUAUAAUAUGUUAGGAAGUAUUUCCUAGUCUUCAAUUUUCUGAAAGAGUCGGUAUAGAAUUGGUAUUACUUAUUCUUUAAAUAUUUGAUAGAAUUCAUCAAUUUAGCUAUGCGGACCUGAAGUUUUCUUGUGGGAAGAUUUUUUGUUUAACUAUCAGGUCAAUUUCUUUGGCAGAUAUAGAAUUAUUCAUGUAAUCUAUCUCUCCUUGAGUGAGCUGUGGUAUUUAGUGUUUUUCAAGGAAUCAGUUCAUCUAAUCUAAAUUGUCAAGUUUGUUGGCAUAAAGUUAUUCAUAAUAUUCUCUUAUUAGCCUUUUAAUGUCUAUAGUAUCUGUAAUGAUAUCACCUCACAUUGCUACUAUUGUAAUUUGUGUCUUGUCUCUUUAUUAAUCUUCUCAAAGAACCAGCUUUUAGUUUUGUUGAUUUUCUCCAUUGCUUUUCUGCUUUCUAUUUCAUUUUUUCUUCUCCGAUCCUUAUUAUUUUUUUCUCCUUACGUUGGGUUUAAUUUGUAUUUAUUUUUCUUGUUUCUCAAGGUAAAAUCUGAGGUCAUUGAUUUGAGCCCUUUCUUCUUUCCAAGUAUAUAUGAUUAGCGCUAUAAAUUUUUUCCUUAGUACUGCUUUAGCAGUAUCCCACAACAUUUGAUAUAUUGUGCUUUUUUUUUUCCAUUUAGUUCAAUAUAUUUUUUCAUUUCCCCUUUCCUUUUUUUCUUUGGCCCAUGAGUUGUUUAGAAGUGUGUUACUGUCUUUCCAAAUACUUGGACAUUUUCCAGAGGUCUCUCUGUUAUUGGUUUCUAAUGUAAUUCCAUUGUGGUCAGAGUACAUACUUUGUACAAACUGAAUUCUUUUAAAUUUAUUAAGACUCAUUUUAUGACCCAGAAUAUGGAUUAUCUUGGUCAGUAUUCCAUGUGUAUUUGAAAAGUAUAUUUAGCUGUCAUUGGGUGGAGUGUUCUAUAAAUGUCAAUUAAGUCAAGAUGGUUGAUAGUAUUCAAAUCAUCUGUAUCCUUACGGAUUUCUGUCUACUUGUUUUAUAAAUUAUUGAGAGAGAAAGUUAUUGAAAUCUUUGGAUAUCAUUGUGACUUUGCUAUUUUUCCUUGGAGUUCAAUCAGUUUGUGCUUUGUGUAUUUUGAAGCUCUGCUAUUAGACACAUAAGUGUUUAGCAUUAUUAUAGCAUAUUGAUGGAUUGACCUUUUAUCAAUACGAAAUGACUUUUUAAUUCCCGCUAAUAUCCUUCCUUCUGUAAUCCAUUUUGCCUGAUAUUAAUAUGCAGUAUUCUCUUAACUAAUGUUAAUGUGUUAUAUCUUUUUCCAGCCUUUUACUUUUAACAGUUUGUGUCUUUAUGUGUAAAGCACAUUUCUUGUAGGCAGGAUAUAGUUGGGUUUCCUCAACAUAGGUAGUCUACCAAGCUGUGCCUGUGUUUCCCCUCCCCGUGCCAUGACCUAAAAACUCUUUAGAUAAUAAGACAGGGCACACUUGGGGUUCAUUUUGUUUCUUUCCUAUGUCUCAGGAACAGAGCUUGAACUAGAGUAAGAUAAGUGAAGCCCCUAUGACAAAAAAAAUUUAAGGCAGAAAUCACUGUCAGAUGCACAAUUUUGCAAGUGAAAGCCUCCUUAGAUUUUUGUACCCUAAGCAGCUGACUCUUAGGAAGAUACUAAUUCUCAGGGUUGUGUAAGUGCAGGGUUAGCUCCUGAGAGUAGAUGUCUUUUUAAAUCCUGUUCGGUAGGGGCUUCACUCAGCUCAAUAUAGUCCUGCCCCUGCUUAAGGAUCACCAUCCUUCAUUCCUGGUGUCUAGUGUCUUGAAAACCAUUUUUAAAGUUAUAUUCUCUCUGGAAUUUUGGUUAUUUCAAUUGGGAGGGUAAAUCCAGCCUCUGAUACUACAUCUUUUCUGGAAACAGAAGUCUAGACUUACUCAUUAUAAGAUAAAAAUUCCACAUAUAGAGCUACCUGCCUGAAAUAAAAAUGCUUGCAGGCCCUCCUCUGAAGACUUCAGCAAAAGAUUGAUCUUCCUUCAUGCAAUGAUCAGUUCUGAAAAAGACUUCAAGAAACUGACUAAUCGCGAUGGCUGCCCCUGACGGGAGGGUAGUCUCCAGACCCCAGAGACUUGGUCAGGGGUCUGGCCAGGGGCCAAAGGGGAGUGGAGCCUGCCUGCAUCCCCUGGACAGCCUGGAGCAGAAGGAGACUCAGGAGCAAACGUCGGGCCAGCUAGUCAUGCUGAGGAAGGCACAGGAGUUCUUUCAGACCUGUGAUGCUGAAGGCAAGGGCUUCAUCGCCAGGAAGGAUAUGCAGAGGCUGCAUAAGGAGCUACCGCUCAGCCUGGAGGAACUGGAGGAUGUGUUUGAUGCCCUGGAUGCUGAUGGCAAUGGCUAUCUGACCCCACAGGAGUUCACUACUGGAUUUAGUCACUUCUUCUUCAGCCAGAAUAACCCAAGUCAGGAAGAUGCAGGUGAACAGGUGGCCCAGCGCCAUGAAGAGAAGGUGUAUCUGUCCAGAGGGGAUGAGGAUCUGGGCGACAUGGGCGAAGAUGAGGAAGCCCAGUUCCGGAUGCUGAUGGACAGACUUGGAGCCCAAAAGGUGUUGGAAGAUGAAAGUGAUGUCAAGCAGCUCUGGUUGCAGCUGAAGAAGGAGGAACCUCAUUUACUGUCCAACUUUGAAGACUUCCUGACCAGAAUCAUCUCCCAGCUCCAAGAAGCCCAUGAGGAGAAGAAUGAACUGGAGUGUGCCCUAAAAAGGAAAAUUGCUGCUUAUGAUGAAGAAAUCCAGCAUCUCUAUGAGGAGAUGGAACAACAAAUCAAAAGUGAGAAGGAGCAGUUUCUCCUGAAGGACACAGAGAGGUUUCAAGCCCGCAGUCAAGAGCUGGAGCAGAAACUGUUAUGUAAGGAGCAGGAGCUGGAGCAGCUCACCCAGAAGCAGAAAAGGCUGGAAGGUCAGUGCACAGCCCUGCAUCAUGACAAGCAUGAGACCAAGGCUGAGAAUACCAAGCUGAAACUCACUAACCAGGAGCUGGCCCGGGAGCUGGAGCGGACUUCCUGGGAGCUCCAGGAUGCUCAGCAGCAGUUGGAAAGCCUCCAGCAAGAGGCCUGCAAACUCCACCAAGAGAAGGAGAUGGAAGUGUACCGUGUGACGGAGAGUCUACAGCGUGAGAAGGCCGGGCUCCUCAAGCAGCUGGAUUUCCUAAGGGAAAGGAACAAGCACCUUCGGGAUGAACGGGACAUAUGUUUUCAGAAAAAUAAGGCAGCCAAGGCAAACACAGCUGCUUCCAGGGCAAGUUGGAAAAAGAGAUCUGGCUCUGUGAUAGGCAAAUAUGUGGACAGCAGAGGGAUUCUUAGGAGUAGCCAGUCAGAGGAGGAGGAGGAGGUGUUUGGCAUCCCAAGGAGAAGCUCCCUGGGCCUGAGUGGAUAUCCCCUAACAGAAGAGGAGCCAGGAACCGGGGAGCCAGGGCCUGGGGGUCCGUACCCCCGGCCGCUCCGCAGAAUCAUCUCCGUUGAAGAAGACCCCCUGCCCCAGCUCCUGGAUGGUGGCUUUGAGCAACCCCUGAGCAAAUGCUCAGAAGAGGAAGAGGUCUCUGACCAGGGGGUACAGGGACAAAUCCCGGAGGCCCCACCCUUGAAACUCACCCCCACAUCCCCCCGAGGGCAGCCUGUUGGAAAAGAAGCCCUGUGUAAGGAGGAAAGCUCUCCCUCUGCCCCUGACCGGCUCUUCAAGAUUGUGUUCGUGGGCAAUUCCGCGGUGGGGAAGACAUCCUUCCUGAGGAGAUUCUGUGAGGACCGGUUCUCCCCAGGCAUGGCGGCCACUGUGGGCAUUGAUUACCGUGUGAAGACGUUGAAUGUGGACAACUCUCAGGUGGCCCUGCAGCUGUGGGACACGGCUGGGCAGGAGAGGUACCGGUGCAUCACCCAGCAGUUCUUCAGAAAGGCAGAUGGUGUCAUCGUCAUGUACGAUCUCACAGACAAGCAGUCGUUCCUGUCGGUCCGGCGGUGGCUGAGCAGCGUGGAGGAAGCUGUGGGAGACCGGGUGCCUGUUCUUCUGCUGGGUAAUAAGCUUGACAACGAGAAGGAGCGGGAAGUCCCCCGGGGCCUCGGAGAGCAGCUUGCCACGGAGAACAAUCUGAUCUUCUAUGAAUGCAGCGCCUACUCUGGUCACAACACCAAAGAGUCCCUGCUCCAUCUGGCCAGGUUCCUCAAGGAGCAAGAAGACACAGUGAGAGAGGACACCAUUCAGGUCGGCCACCCUGCUAAGAAGAAAUCCUGCUGUGGCUGAUAGGGUCCUACAAGGACUGCCCCCAGC